AGAAGCAUCCGAGGCAUUAAAGCAUCCGAGGGAGCCGGAGGGGAGGAGAAUGGAGUGACAGAGACACGCGGAGGGUGGGGGGUGGGGGGGAGCGUGUUGAGGGAGGGGGGAGGGGGGACACAGAGGGAGGAAGAAGCGGCGGCGGCGGCGGCGGCGGCGGCGGCUCCUCUUUGCAGAGGGGGAAACUCUUGGGCUGAGAGCAGGAAUAAUGCGGUAGGCAAGGCGGGCUGCUGGCUCCCCCGGCUCCGGCAGCAGCGGCGGCAGCCCGAGCAGCGGCAGCAGCAGCGGCAGCACCCCAGGCGCUGACAGCCCCGCCGGCCGGCUCCGUUGCUGACCGCCGACUGUCAAUGGAGCUGGAAAACAUCGUGGCCAACACGGUCUUGCUGAAAGCCAGGGAAGGGGGCGGAGGAAAGCGCAAAGGGAAAAGCAAGAAGUGGAAAGAAAUCCUGAAGUUCCCUCACAUUAGCCAGUGUGAAGACCUCCGAAGGACCAUAGACAGAGAUUACUGCAGUUUAUGUGACAAGCAGCCAAUCGGGAGGCUGCUUUUCCGGCAGUUUUGUGAAACCAGGCCUGGGCUGGAGUGUUACAUUCAGUUCCUGGACUCCGUGGCAGAAUAUGAAGUUACUCCAGAUGAAAAACUGGGAGAGAAAGGGAAGGAAAUUAUGACCAAGUACCUCACCCCAAAGUCCCCUGUUUUCAUAGCCCAAGUUGGCCAAGACCUGGUCUCCCAGACGGAGGAGAAGCUCCUACAGAAGCCGUGCAAAGAACUCUUUUCUGCCUGUGCACAGUCUGUCCACGAGUACCUGAGGGGAGAACCAUUCCACGAAUAUCUGGACAGCAUGUUUUUUGACCGCUUUCUCCAGUGGAAGUGGUUGGAAAGGCAACCGGUGACCAAAAACACUUUCAGGCAGUAUCGAGUGCUAGGAAAAGGGGGCUUCGGGGAGGUCUGUGCCUGCCAGGUUCGGGCCACGGGUAAAAUGUAUGCCUGCAAGCGCUUGGAGAAGAAGAGGAUCAAAAAGAGGAAAGGGGAGUCCAUGGCCCUCAAUGAGAAGCAGAUCCUCGAGAAGGUCAACAGUCAGUUUGUGGUCAACCUGGCCUAUGCCUACGAGACCAAGGAUGCACUGUGCUUGGUCCUGACCAUCAUGAAUGGGGGUGACCUGAAGUUCCACAUCUACAACAUGGGCAACCCUGGCUUCGAGGAGGAGCGGGCCUUGUUUUAUGCGGCAGAGAUCCUCUGCGGCUUAGAAGACCUCCACCGUGAGAACACCGUCUACCGAGAUCUGAAACCUGAAAACAUCCUGUUAGAUGAUUAUGGCCACAUUAGGAUCUCAGACCUGGGCUUGGCUGUGAAGAUCCCCGAGGGAGACCUGAUCCGCGGCCGGGUGGGCACUGUUGGCUACAUGGCUCCAGAGGUCCUGAACAACCAGAGGUACGGCCUGAGCCCCGACUACUGGGGCCUUGGCUGCCUCAUCUAUGAGAUGAUCGAGGGCCAGUCGCCGUUCCGCGGCCGCAAGGAGAAGGUGAAGCGGGAGGAGGUGGACCGCCGGGUCCUGGAGACGGAGGAGGUGUACUCCCACAAGUUCUCCGAGGAGGCCAAGUCCAUCUGCAAGAUGCUGCUCACGAAAGAUGCGAAGCAGAGGCUGGGCUGCCAGGAGGAGGGGGCUGCAGAGGUCAAGAGACACCCCUUCUUCAGGAACAUGAACUUCAAGCGCUUAGAAGCCGGGAUGUUGGACCCUCCCUUCGUUCCAGACCCCCGCGCUGUGUACUGUAAGGACGUGCUGGACAUCGAGCAGUUCUCCACUGUGAAGGGCGUCAAUCUGGACCACACAGACGACGACUUCUACUCCAAGUUCUCCACGGGCUCUGUGUCCAUCCCAUGGCAAAACGAGAUGAUAGAAACAGAAUGCUUUAAGGAGCUGAACGUGUUUGGACCUAAUGGUACCCUCCCGCCAGAUCUGAACAGAAACCACCCUCCGGAACCGCCCAAGAAAGGGCUGCUCCAGAGACUCUUCAAGCGGCAGCAUCAGAACAAUUCCAAGAGUUCGCCCAGCUCCAAGACCAGUUUUAACCACCACAUAAACUCAAACCAUGUCAGCUCGAACUCCACCGGAAGCAGCUAGUUUCGGCUCUGGCCUCCAAGUCCACAGUGGAACCAGCCCAGACCCUUCUCCUUAGAAGUGGAAGUAGUGGAGCCCCUGCUCUGGUGGGGCUGCCAGGGGAGACCCCGGGAGCCGGGGAAGGAGGCCGUCCAUCCCGUCGACGUAGAACCUCGAGGUUUCUCAAAGAAAUUUCCACUCAGGUCUGUUUUCCGAGGCGGCCCCGGCCGGGGUGGAUUGGAUUUGUCUUUGGUGAACAUUGCAAUAGAAAUCCAAUUGGAUACGACAACUUGCACGUAUUUUAAUAGCGUCAUAACUAGAACUGAAUUUUGUCUUUAUGAUUUUUAAAGAAAAGUUUUGUAAAUUUCUCUACUGUCUCAGUUUACAUUUUGUAUAUUUGUAUUUAAAUGAAAGUGAGACUUUGAGGGUGUAUAUUUUCUGUGCAGCCACUGUUAAGCCAUGUGUUCCAAGGCAUUUUAGCGGGGAGGGGGUUAUCAAAAAAAAAAAAAUGUGACUCAAGACUUCCAGAGCCUCAAAUGAGAAAAUGUCUUUAUUAAAUGUAGAAAGUGAUCCAUACUUCACCUUUGAAGGAUUGGUUGUAUUUACCCACAUCUAUCUCUGGAGCCAUUUCCUCACAUUGGUGUCACCCUUCUGUCGGCUUGGAACAAUCUGAAUUAAAUGUUCCAGACACACGUGGGACUUCCCCCUCCCAGCCAGAAUGUCCUCUCCUGGGGCCCUCGGAGUCGCCUAGGCUGAGCCCUUCUCCUCGAGGGGCACGCCGAGCCACUGUCGCACCCACCUCUGUCUGCUCUUCCUUCAGGAAGGCGGCUGGCACGCGGAUCUAGGUGUUUGCAGCCUGGUGGGCGAUGGGCCUCUUUCCUUCUAAGCAGGUCCUGACUGCUAAAGCCAGUCAUUUGCAAGAGGUUUGCAUUGGGGGAUUUUUGCUCUAUUUUUAACAGAAGCAUAGGACCGUAAAGAUGUGUCAUGAAACCCCAAGUGUCCCAAAGCCUCGGGGCCCACAGGAGCAUCGGGAAGUGAGGCAGUGCGCUCAUCCUGACGGAGCAGCGUCGUGUCUGUAGCGGGGAGGGAGGCUGGCCCAGGGGCCCGGCAUGUUCCUGAAGCGUUCACAGGGUUUUGAGACCUUCACAGCCCCAUCAAUGUGCUGGCCCAUGUGGCAUGGAUGGGGUAGUCUCUCUGGGCAAAUGAGAGGCCCAAGGAGAGACCAAGCCACCAAAGGGCUCAAGACAAAGUCACUGUUCCUUCCCCAGGAAGGUGGGGCAGAGGCAAGAUCUAUCGGACAUUUCAAAGUUUCAGGCAGGAGCUCCUAGAGGACUUGGUGGCUUUGCCAGCCCAGGGGCCUCUGAAGGCAGCCCCCAGACCCUUGUAGCAGGGCUGUCCAUCCCCAGGGAGCAGCUGGCCACCUCCUCCUGCCUCGAAGAAGUGACCAGGGGCCAAUCUGCUCCCACCUCCCGUCCAGGACAGGGUGAACAUUUGACCUCACUGUCCCCUGCCCGGCUGAGUCCCUGAUGUCUGACUGUGCCACCCAGCAGCUGCCAGGGUCUCUCACCAUGUGGACCCUGCCCUAGCUGCAGCUGCACCUCCUGUCAAAAGUGCAGACUCGCAGGUUCCACCCCAAACCACAGAAUGGGAAUGCCUGGGAGCCCACCCCUGCUGUGGGCUCUCAGCGGGGCUUUGGGGGUGAUCAUCCCAAACACAUUUCUCUGGAUGACGCAGGCAGCAUUGGAGCAUGAGCCGUGGGGAGGACAGUCGUGAGCACACCAGCUGUGAGGCCCGGUUUCCAUGCCUAACCCCCGGACUCUACCCCUGGGUCCUGGGGCGUACCGCUAAAAGGGUCCUGGCCUUUGGGACUGAUCAUUUUGAGGCCCUUUUACAAAGAAAUGGGGGAGAAGAAAUAGCUGGGCUUCCCUCAAAUCUUUUUAAUGUGCAGUAUUUUUUUGUUCAAGACCAGCUCUUGUUUUAUGAGGCUCCUUCCAUUACCUUUCUUGGGCUGAAUGCAAAACAAAUACAGCCACAUUCAAGUCUUCCAAGGAAGUAGAAAACUCUUUGAAUGGUAUCUUAAGAUCCUUAAGCUCUUGCUGAACUUCCUUUUUCAAUGAAAAGAAGGACCAUCAUCCUAGGAUGGUCACCAGCCCAAGCCACCACCCCAGCCACCCAUCCAGGAGGUUGGUUCCUUUUGCCCAGUUCAUAGCAGCUCAGUCCUUACCAGAUGGAUUCUUGGUGUUGGGAAGCAGCCUCUUUUUAUUCCUGAAAGGCAAUGCCCUGUCCGUUUGCAGUAGAGAAUCCCCAGGGAGCAAGAAAGAUGACAGAAGUGUGGCUGCCGUGUUUCUAGGUCAUGAGAGCUCUGGCGAUACUACCACAAGGCCUGCACGUGGACUCUAUGAUAACUUGAGUCUUCCAUCAUGUUUGCCACCAGCCCUCCCUGAGUGCCCAGAGGAGAUGGGGGCAGAGUCACUUGGCCUACUAAAGCCUCCUGUUCCUUCUGGCUCAUGCAUUGCUUUGUGGUAAGAGAAAGGAAGUCUUUAGAACAGCGCCUGGGAAUCAGCCCUUCUCCCUACUGAGUCCCCAGUCCUGUCCCUUCCCUGACUCGCUCCUCCUCCAACCUUGGUUUCUAUAGCUGCAUUUUUUUUUUUUUUUUUUUUUGAGACAAGAUCUCAUUGUGUUCCCCAGGCUGAAGUGCAGUGGCAUGAUUCUGGCUCACUGCAGCCUCAAACUCCUGAGUCCAAGCUAUCCUCCUGCCUCAGCCUCCGAGGUAGCUGGGACCAUAGGCGUGCACCACCAUACUCAGCUAAUUUUUAAAAUUUUUUGUAGAGAUGGGGGGGGGGUCUCCCCAUGUUGCCCAGGCUGGCCUCGAAUUCCUGAGCCCAAGCUAUCCUCCUGCCUCAGCCUCCCAAAGUGCUGAGGUUAUAGGUGUGAGCCACUGUCCCUGGCCUAUACGGUCAUUUUUUAAAAGAUAUUUUAAAAUUAAAAGCAAACAACACUGUCCACCCAUCUACCUGUCCAGGAUAAGGCAUAUUUGGACGGUGAACGGAUUUACUCUCGUUCAUGCAUUUGAGCGCUUCACAGAAGAGUCUUUCUUGCUCCAGGCAUGACAUUUUUUUUCACCAGACGUUCACUGACUUCGUGACUUUGAGGUGAGACAUGGGAUCUCUCAGAAGCGUCUCUGCAUCUGCAUUUCAGGAGAUGAGCUGCUGUCCCUGGUGGACAGAGGCGGUCUCUGCCAUGGUCACCAUGAUGCCCUACAAGUGUUUAUUGAGUCCCCUGGGGGGCACCCAGAAUACCACCCAAAAUAGCAAGAAGACCCGGUCCCCGCCUUGCGGACGAUGCACUCACAUGCCACAGCAACCCAUUCUCGCCUCUUCCUUGGCCGGGAACCCGGGGCUCUAGGGCUGCUCGCUGCUGCUGUGGCCUGCGCAGCCACGGGAGGCUUCCUGAAAGGCAUUGCUCGGAGGGGCGGGGGCGGGGAGGCCUAGCCUGCCCCACAGACACAGCUGUGAGGCCUGGGUCAUACACAUACCAGCAAGCAGCUGCCGAGACAAAUGGUGGUGGGAAGUCCUGGGAACACACACAGCCUUUGCAUUGACAGCACAAGUAGGAUCAGAGCCCAGGUGAGCCCCUGAGGAUACCGAGGCCUUCCCUCCCUGAGGCCCGCAAGUCUCCAUGCGUCUCCCGGGAGCCUGGCCCCGCUGCAGAAAUCCCUUCUCUUCCUCCACACCCUGUCCUUUCCCCAAAGGCUCGUGUUAUCAGUUCCAGCUACCCAUCGACUUUCCCACCGAGCCGCUGCCCUCAAAACGGAGGGGGCACCGCAGCCUCCUUGAGCCUGGCAUCCCAGGCCUUGCCAAAGGGGACGGUGGCUUCCUGGAUAAUUGGAAAUCUCUGAGAAGAAGAGGAAACACCUGAGUGACACUCAGCUGUCCUCUGGGGUCCCCUGGUGUGCAUGCACGUCCUCCUGAAUACCUGUACUUCCAAGAGGUGGUCUCCUGUUUUCAUAACCCAACACUCUGAGAUAGGAUCUUCCAACUUUUUAGCCCCGGCUGUGGAAAGAUAGUGAGUAUGAAGUCUUUGUGCAUUUGGAAGUGACAUCGCUGUGUGGAUUAUGAAUACAGAGAGCUGCCAUCUUCCUGAUCACAAUAGACCACGAUUGCAAAGCCUCCUCUCCCAGAGACCCCUUCUGCGCCUGCCCUCCCCACCCACCACCCAGCUGUUGAAGCUCAGCGUGUGCAAGUCAGACCCUGCACAGGCCGGGGGUGUCUCACCUGGCCUAAACGUAAAGGCUUGUGCCGGAGACAGUGAUUGAAAACAUUUGAAAAGCCAGCUCUCCCUGGCAGAGAAAGACACUUCCCCCCCAAAGUGGAAUUUAGAUGUCUUUCCCUAGUCCAUCAAGAAGUCAUUUUUGUAACAGUCCCUAAGCGAGUGUUCUCAAUUAGAAGAGUUUAGUGGCUUUUGGUGUUGUUAAAAUAAUAAGAAUCCUUCUAGCAUCCAAAGCUUUCUAAUUUUUUUCAGGGAGAUUUGGACAUUAAUGAAUGGAAACUUCCACAGUGGCGGUCACUCCUGAAGGCAGCGGCUUCUGUUCUCCCGCUGCUGUAACUCUGUGUGUUCCGUCUAUCGCGUCACAGUGCCGCUGGAUCUAGAUGGAGCCACUGUUGUUGUUUUUAAAAGAGAAAUAAAUUCCUUAAUGGAAGUA